GUACGCUCGCAAGGCGCUCGCAGACUCCGGAGUCGCCAACAUGUCGACCGCCAUGAAUUUCGGGACCAAGAGCUUCCAGCCGCGGCCCCCGGACAAGGGCAGCUUCCCGCUGGAUCACUUAGGUGAAUGUAAAAGCUUUAAAGAGAAAUUCAUGAAGUGUCUUCAUAACAAUAAUUUUGAAAAUGCUUUGUGCAGAAAGGAAUCAAAAGAAUAUUUAGAAUGCAGGAUGGAGAGAAAAUUGAUGCUACAAGAACCAUUGGAGAAACUGGGAUUUGGAGACUUGACUAGUGGAAAAUCAGAGGCAAAAAAAUGAAUUUUGAUGAGAAGACCCCUGGGCCGUGUUCAGUGGUCUCUCAGGACGGAGGGCAUCAUCCUGCCUCUUAGGUUGGCUGAGGCCUGCGUGUGGUGUCCUUAGAAAUGGGCUUCGAAUAGAAGCUCCAGCCCUGUGGGGGCGUCUCCUGGGUAGGGAGUGGCGUCCCGUUUUCCCUUAGGAGGGUGUUUCUGCAUUGAACCCCUGAGUGGGACGGCGUUCCCGGCAAAGCUGGGAGGGAGGCGAGCGUGGGGCAAGACCCUUGUCUUCGAGGCCGGGGCCCUCUUGUAUGGGGCGGUUUUAUGUUGCAGUCCUCUGAUACUUUCUGAGUUCAAAGAGGUAAAUGUAUAAAUUUCAGUCCCUUCUGAACACAGAUAUCAUCAGAAAAUUACCAUUCCCUAGCAGGAUGUUUUCGUGUUUGUAUUCGUAUAUGCCAGUUCAUUUCCUUUGAAAAAAAAAAAAAGUGGAACACAAAGUAGGAAGUGAGAACCUUCUGGCUUUGGAUGGAUUGACUUCUUGAUUCUUUCUGGUUUUGCCUGAACACCAAGUAGCUUCAUAAUCAAAGGGUCAUUUUCUGGUUUGUAUCAGACCGUAUUUAUAAAGUUGGGUAUUUAAUUUCAGUAACUCCUGUAUUUUAACAGAAAAAGAACCUGAGUCCAUUUGCAGUUAGGCUCGCACCAGCUGUCUUCUGUGCCAGCCAGCUCCGCCCGAGACCCCGGCACGUGUUCGCAGCACAGCCUGGCAGGGGCCCUGAGCGGAGUUCUCAGCCCGUCUGUGCCAAAGUUGCCUGUGGGUCACGGAAACCCGGCCCAUGUCCACCCAGUGCGUCAGGCCAGCCGGGGCCCAAACCUGUGGAUGGAACGCAGGUGCCUGCACAUCUGGGGCCUCAGCCAGACCUGUCUCCUUCCCAGGCACUGUCGGAAAGGGGCUGGCUCCUGUCUGGUCAGUGGAGGAUGGUGGCAGGAGACGGGGUGGGGAGGUCCAGGUCACGUCCUCUCUGGCGACCCUGGCAGUGGCUGUCUCCAAGCCCUGGCAGGUGGGGCCACCAAUCUGGCCGACCUCAGGCUCUGGGAAACAGGCUGCCCUCGUCCCUCUGCCUGUGGGUGGCUGAGGCUUCUCAGCCCAUCUCCAGUUCUCUGCAGCAAAGGCCCUCUGUUUCUGUCCUGCAGUGGUGGCCCUUUCGUGGUUAAACAUGUCCCUCCCCUCCUCACAGAACUGAGUACCUAUUGCGGCUGGGCCCGCCCAACCCUGUGUCCCUGCACCCAUGGGUUCUACCACCUGAUUCGGCUGCAGCUGUCACUGUCCCGUGUCUGCUCUCUGUCAGGCCUCUGAGUGCUGCAGACGUAUUAACAUAUCACCGCUAGUUGAUGGAAAGUCUUGUUUCUUAUUAGAAUAUUUUGUGUAGGCACAGGGUUGCCCCAGCACUGUCUAUAGCAACCCCAGUGUCCUCACAGUGCACGUGAGCCGUGACGCAGCCACCGUGGAGUCGGCGCUGACGCGGUGUGGCCACGUGCCAUGAGCUCGCCAACGCAGUGCGGCUAUAUGGCGUGAGCUUACUGUGAAGUGGAGACAGGCAGGGACACAGGAAACUACAAACGAGAAAUCCAGAAGGAGGAGCUGGAACUGAUGGGCAUAGCCGGCCGCGAGCCCCUCCGAGCACCCCUGGGGGUGGAGUUCUGGCUGUCAUGGCAGAGGGUUUCACAUGCUCAAAAAGUAAAUGAACCAGGAUGUGAGGGGAACACAACAGACCAUGCCGACGGAGCUCCCGGGCCCAGGCCGGGGCCUCUUCCCAUCGCACUCUGACCCGCCGUCGGGAGUGCCCAGGCCCGGGUCGGGCCUGCCUCUCCGCUCGCACCGCACUCUGACCCAUCAGGAGUGUGGGGAAGACCGUCGACCAAAGGUGGGAAAGACAGGAAAGAUACUGUACUCUAAGUAGUAAAUUUGUUUUUUGCGUGGACGAUUCUGAAGCUGUAUUCUGAGAUGGAAAAAACUAGAAAUACAUCGUGGAUGAUGAGAGCCAGGUGUAUUGAGCUCCUGCUUUUCUAACGUACAAAGGUAACUGGAUAGAGAAACGGAGUGAUCGCCCUCACCUGGCCAGGGUGUGCUCCGAGACCCCAGCAGGUGCCGAAGCCGCGGAUAGUCCCGAAUCCUGUCCAGGCGCUGUUUUUUCCUGUACGUACCUGUGAUCAAGUCUGAGAUGUGACAGCAAAACUGACAGAACUUCGUGCUUCCCUCUUCAAAAUGUCACAGAUGGGCACUGUGUUCUUACCGGAGAUCUUAGCAACCUCGGCAUCUGGCUGUUUUUCUUAUAGGUCAGGAGUUUCCACCUUUUCCCUUAAAGGAAGCGCUUGGCAGCUUCUCUGGUGUGUCUGAGUCGCCAGCAUCACCACUGUCCUGUUCUGGGGCCAUUCUUAAGUAAAAUAAAAGCUUCUUGGACCCAAGCACCACAUCACCGCGAUGGCUGGUCUGAUCACCGAGAUGGCUGCUGAGUGCCUGGCAGGCAGGGUGGCGUGGAUGGCCCGAAACGCUGGACGGAGGGAGGGUUGAUGUCCCAGCAGGACGGCUGCUCAGAACAGCACAGAAUCAAAAACUCAUGAAUGGUUUAUUUCUGGAAUUUUCCACUUAGUAUUUUUGGACUGUGGCUGACCAUGGGUAACUGAAACCGUGUGUAAGGGGGACUGUUGUGAGGGGCUGUGCACAAAUGCUUCCCAGCUCUUGAGGGCCUGGACGCAGUGACCCGUGCACUCAGGGUCUUGGCCCUGAUACCAUUCUGUAACCAAAAGGAACCAGGGCCAGGCCAGAGAAGGUAUCAGAUGAGCUAGAGAGUGAAGAAUUGCUGGGAUGAGGAGACUUGUUGAAAUAACACGGGGGGAUGGGAAGGAGCAUACGGUGGCCAGCCUGGGGCAGUGUGAGCGUGAAAAUAAACAGGCUGGGCGCAGCGGCUCACGCCUGCAAUCCCAGCACUUUAGGAGGCCAAGGUGGGAGGAUCACUUGAGGCUAGGAGUUCAAGACCAGCCUGGGCAACAUGGGUGAAACCCUGUCUCUACAAAACAAGAAAAGUCAGCCGUGCGUGGUGUCACCCGCCUGUAGUCCCAGAUACUCAGGAAGCUGAGGCAGGAGGAUCACUUGAGCCAGAGGUUAAGUCUGCAGUGAGCUGUGAUUGUACCACUGCUCUCCAGCCUGAGCAACAGAGCCGGACCCUGUCUCACCAAAGGAAAAAAAAAAAAAAAAAAGAAAGAAAAUUAAUUAUUGUAAUGGGCUGUAGCCCUCAGAAUAAAUUGAUAUCCAGUAGUCUAUACAACAUAAGUAAUUGCGUAAACAUGUCAGUGGGGGGAGGGCCAGGUCUGUCUUAUUAAUUCUAAUAUAGAAGAAAUUUUGGGAACAGGAAACUGCUGUUGCAGAAACCACACUGGUGACAGGUGCAGAUUACAACCCUCAGCGGGCCGGGCGCCAGUGGCUCACGCCUAUAAUCCCAACACUUUGGGAGGCCGAGGCAGGCAGAUCACUUGAGGCCAGGAGUUCAAGGCCAGCCUGGCCAACAUGGAGAAACCCUGUCUCUACUAAAAAUACAAAAAUUAGCUGGGGCUGGUGGCGUGUGUCUGUAAUCCAGCUAUUCGGGAGGCCGAGGUGGGAGAAUUGCCUAAACCAGGAGGCAGAGGUUGCAGUGAGCAGGGAUUGUGCCACCACACUCCAGCCUGGGCGACAGAACCGUCUCAAAAAAAAACCCUCAGUUGCCAUGAAGUGAGUGGUGACGUGUGGUGUGAAGCAGGUGUCUGCUGUCUUGAGAAACCUCCCCUUGAGAUGCAUAGUGACCUCCGAGGAGACAGUCAUGUCACAGCAGAACGGCAGAGGCCCCCUUAACCCAGCAGCCACCGCCGGGAGCGAGCCGCACAGGCCGCACCGACCUGGGGGCGUCCCUGAGGGCACGGUAUCACCUCUGGUUCUCUUGCCCAACUGCAUGGCCUGAAUGUAAUCCCAAGGAGACAACAGACACAGACCCAAACCGAGGAGCCUUCUGCGAAGUGACUGGCAGCGCUGGCCCAGUGUUAUGUAAGAUGUUAUUUGGGGAACUGGGUAUACACACUGUCCUAUUUUUGGAACUUUUUGGAAGUCUGAAAUUAUUUUGAAAUGAGGAAAAAAAAAUAUGCUUUGUAUGAAACUAUAGUGGAAUAGAUUGAGUCGAUUCUCGUUUCAAAAUAACUUCAAAGAGUUUCCAAUAGGCAUGAUGCCGGCAUGAAUGGUUUCAGCAGGUCACAGGCAGAGAAGCCGGAAUCCCAAAAUAGCGCCAUUGUGUGGACAACCUGACUCCUUACAAACGUGCAGUGGCUUCCCAACGCUGCCUUUGAGUUUCUGGGUCUGGCUGCUGAAUGUGUUGUGCUUAAGAAUCCAGACACCCUGCUGUUCCUGCCAGAGCUUCUCACGAGAUAUUUCGGGUAGUUCAUCAUCUGUCAUGUGCAGAAUGCAUUUUAUUUCUCAUAGACGCUUGUCAUGAUAAGCUGGCCACAUUAUUAAAAGGCUCCCAAAGACAA